GGGGCGAACCAAUUCCUCCGUUGCGGCCCCCACCUGCAGUAUGGAGUCGUCUCGGGGGCGGCCCGGGCCCGAGACGGACCUUCUGGCUGUAGCGGAACAUCAGGCCCUAGUCUUUGGCGGCGGGCCGGGCCGAACGUCCUCUGAGCCGCCCGCAGGCCUCCGGGUGUCCGGGGAGGAAGAGACCGAGAACGUUGGGGGCGCGAACCGCCACCCCAGGACGUCCCCGAAGACGUCAAGCUGCGGCGUCGUCCACCGGCCGGAACGGGAGGCUCUGGAGAACGAGCCCGGCCCUCAAGGGACGCUGUCUGGGGCCGGGAGCCGCAGGGGGGCGCCGGGUGCAGAGCACGAACCUUCCCUGUCCUCCCGGCACAAGAACCCGGCGCCGCCCGAGGGCAAGCCCUCCUCCGGGAGGGACUGCCGUCGAGGGGGACCAGGCGGCGGGAUGGAUGUUGAGCAGCAGGAGGAGGAAGACAACGACGAGGAGGCGGCCGCGGGCAGCAGAGCCGGCCGCUCGUUCUCCAGCCGUCUUCAGGACAGCCGCAGCCUGGACGGGCUGAGCGAGGCGUGCGGUGGCGCCGGGUCCUCAGGGAGUGCCGAGUCCGGCGCGGGCGGCGGACGCCGCGCCACCAUCUCCAGUCCCCUGGAGCUCGAAGGCACAGUGAGCCGCCACGGCGACCUUACCCACUUUGUCGCCAACAACCUGCAACUCAAGAUCCGUCUGAGCGGCGCGCCUCCACCCCCGCCUUCUGCCCCUGCGCGGCCCUGCCCAGCGCCUGCACCCACACCCACACCGGCCAUUCCCCCAAUCGACCCCGAGGUGCUGCGGGAUCUGGAGCGGUUGAGUCGGGAGCUGGGAGGCCGGGUGGACCGUCUGCUUCGCGGUCUGGGUGGCGCGGUGCAGGAGCUGACGGCGCUGAGCGUGGGUUGCAUCCAGACCUACCGCGAUGCUGUGGACUCCUUAGGUGAAGCCGUGGACAUGAGCAUCAAGGGCAUGUACACCCUGCUGGCGCGCUGCGAGGAGCUGGAGCGGGCUCUGCAGCCGGUUCAGGGGCUGGCGCGCCAAGUCCGGGAUAUCCGACGUACUCUGGAGGUGUUGGAGGCCCUGUGCAAGUGACCAGGAGGACAGGAGAGGCCGGUCCUGGCCAGGGCAGGGCCCAGCAGGACCCUAAGGACUCUUCAGGGAGUCCUGGUGGGAAGUGCCCACUGAGGGGAGGCCUGUGUGUUGGAGGCUCUUCCAGAUGCGUUCAGCUGGCCCGUGCCCACUCGCUGGGCCUUAGGCUGGUGUAUGUGGGGAAGUUCUAACGGCUCUCCUGGUGGGAAGGGAUGUUGCUCUGCUUGUAUUCAGUUGGCCAUCUGUAGCUACCCUGUUCUUCCCAACUCUCCUCCCUAGCUAGAGCACCAGCCCUGGGAACACGGGGCUUUAGGUCUGCUUGAAGGUGAGGACGUGACUCCCACAUGUAAUCAGGAGAAAGGGACAGAGGAAGCCCCAGCCCCCACUGUGGCUAUCCUGACUCCAGUGGCCACAUCUCAGGUGCCAGGGGCUGUGGGAGCUUGUGCCGUCCUUGGCCAAACACCCCGCAGGCAAAGAUGCACCCCUGCUGAUGGAGAGCCUUCUGCUUCUGCCCUCUGGCCCUCUACCAUACCACUUCCCCAGCCAGAACCGGCGUGCAGCUAGGAGGAAUGGGUUGCACGGCGGAGGGGGUGAGGUGGGAGGCGUCUCACUGCUCUCAGGGUUCAGGUAGAAUGUUGCUGGUUUUGAAGCUCACCUGUUGUGGAGUGUUCUAAUCAGUUUUGGCUUUCUGAGUUUUUGUGGAAUUAAAGUGCUGCUGCUGCGAA